ACAGUCGCACGCAGCCAGGCGCGCACUGCACAGCUCUCUUCUCUCGCCGCCGCCCGAGCGCACCCUUCAGCCCGCGCGCCGGCCGUGAGUCCUCGGUGCUCGCCCGCCGGCCAGACAAACAGCCCGCCCGACCCCGUCCCGACCCUGGCCGCCCCGAGCGGAGCCUGGAGGUGAGCGCUGGAAGCCGAGGGAGUGAGCGCGACGAGGGCUGCUCGCCUUCAUUCCCUUCGCGCCCCUCUAAGUAACCAGUCCGCCGACCCCUGACCCACCCCGGAUCCGCGCCCCCAGCCUCCGGCUUGGAAAUAACUCUGGCUUAAACUUCUUCUAAGCCACCGCUGCUCCUCGGCGCUUCGAAAAGUUUCCCGCAAAGCGAAAGAACUAACUUUCUCUUUUGACUUGGGGCGCGAAAGGUUCCUGGUGACGGAGGUCGGGCGUCCACUCUGCCGCCAGCCUCGAGCGCCGCUUCUCUCCGCCGACGGCGCUGGCUUGCCCGGCUGGGAGAGGGCGUAAGCAAAAUGAUGCUUCAACACCCAGGCCAGGUCUCUGCCUCGGAAGUGAGUGCUUCUGCCAUCGUCCCCUGCCUGUCCCCUCCUGGGUCACUGGUGUUUGAGGAUUUUGCUAACCUGACGCCCUUUGUCAAGGAAGAGCUGAGGUUUGCCAUCCAGAACAAGCACCUCUGCCACCGGAUGUCCUCUGCGCUGGAAUCAGUCACUGUCAGCGACAGACCCCUCGGGGUGUCCAUCACAAAAGCCGAGGUAGCCCCUGAAGAAGAUGAAAGGAAAAAGAGGCGACGAGAAAGAAAUAAGAUUGCAGCUGCAAAGUGCCGAAACAAGAAGAAGGAGAAGACGGAGUGCCUGCAGAAAGAGUCGGAGAAGCUGGAAAGUGUGAAUGCUGAACUGAAGGCUCAGAUUGAGGAGCUCAAGAACGAGAAGCAGCAUUUGAUAUACAUGCUCAACCUUCAUCGGCCCACGUGUAUUGUCCGGGCUCAGAAUGGGAGGACUCCAGAAGAUGAGAGAAACCUCUUUAUCCAACAGAUAAAAGAAGGAACAUUGCAGAGCUAAGCAGUCGUGGUAUGGGGGCGACUGGGGAGUCCUCAUUGAAUCCUCAUUUUAUACCCAAAACCCUGAAGCCAUUGGAGAGCUGUCUUCCUGUGUACCUCUAGAAUCCCAGCAGCAGAGAACCAUCAAGGCGGGAGGGCCUGCAGUGAUUCAGCAGGCCCUUCCCAUUCUGCCCCAGAGUGGGUCUUGGACCAGGGCAAGUGCAUCUUUGCCUCAACUCCAGGAUUUAGGCCUUAACACACUGGCCAUUCUUAUGUUCCAGAUGGCCCCCAGCUGGUGUCCUGCCCGCCUUUCAUCUGGAUUCUACAAAAAACCAGGAUGCCCACCGUUAGGAUUCAGGCAGCAGUGUCUGUACCUCGGGUGGGAGGGAUGGGGCCAUCUCCUUCACCGUGGCUACCAUUGUCACUCGUAGGGGAUGUGGAGUGAGAACAGCAUUUAGUGAAGUUGUGCAACGGCCAGGGUUGUGCUUUCUAGCAAAUAUGCUGUUAUGUCCAGAAAUUGUGUGUGCAAGAAAACUAGGCAAUGUACUCUUCCGAUGUUUGUGUCACACAACACUGAUGUGACUUUUAUAUGCUUUUUCUCAGAUCUGGUUUCUAAGAGUUUUGGGGGGCGGGGCUGUCACCACGUGCAGUAUCUCAAGAUAUUCAGGUGGCCAGAAGAGCUUGUCAGCAAGAGGAGGACAGAAUUCUCCCAGCGUUAACACAAAAUCCAUGGGCAGUAUGAUGGCAGGUCCUCUGUUGCAAACUCAGUUCCAAAGUCACAGGAAGAAAGCAGAAAGUUCAACUUCCAAAGGGUUAGGACUCUCCACUCAAUGUCUUAGGUCAGGAGUUGUGUCUAGGCUGGAAGAGCCAAAGAAUAUUCCAUUUUCCUUUCCUUGUGGUUGAAAACCACAGUCAGUGGAGAGAUGUUUGGAAACCACAGUCAGUGGAGCCUGGGUGGUACCCAGGCUUUAGCAUUAUUGGAUGUCAAUAGCAUUGUUUUUGUCAUGUAGCUGUUUUAAGAAAUCUGGCCCAGGGUGUUUGCAGCUGUGAGAAGUCACUCACACUGGCCACAAGGACGCUGGCUACUGUCUAUUAAAAUUCUGAUGUUUCUGUGAAAUUCUCAGAGUGUUUAAUUGUACUCAAUGGUAUCAUUACAAUUUUCUGUAAGAGAAAAUAUUACUUAUUUAUCCUAGUAUUCCUAACCUGUCAGAAUAAUAAAUAUUGGAACCAAGACAUGGUAAA